CUUUAUGACUUGGGCCCCUUGUUAACUGUCUCUUCUCUUACCUUGUUUUUUUCCUCUCUCUCUGUGCUUCAGCCCCACUGGCCCUGUUGCAGUUUCUCCAACCCUCUGCCCCUACAAGAGCCAUUGCAUUUGCUAUUCCCUUUGCAGGAAUCAUGUUCCCCCAGAUGUGUGCAUGGCCCAAUCCCUGAUAUCUUUAUUUAACUAUUUCCUAAUAAUGCCUUUUUGUUGUUGUUGUUAAUGCCUUUUUGUUGUUGUUGUUGUUAUUUGUUUGUUUUGAGUUGGAGUCUUGCUCUGUCGCCAGGCUGGAAUGCAAUGGCGCGAUCUUGGCUCACUGCAACCUCCGCCUCCCGGGUUCAAGCAAUUCUCCUGCCUCAACCUCCCGAGUAGCUGGGACUAAAGGCGUGUGCCACCACGCCCAGCUAAUUUUUGUAUUUUUAGUAGAGACGGGGUUUCACCAUGUUGGCCUGGCUGGUCUUGAACUCCUGACCUCGUGAUCCACCUGCCUCGGUCUCCCAAAGUGCUGAGAUUACAGCCGUGAACCACCACUCCCGGCCCCCCAACCCCCCCCUUUUUUUUUUAAAUCACAUACUAAAUGUGUCAUUUAGAACAUAUGCUUCAAGAGGUCAGGGUUUAUGCUUCCUUUACUGCUAUACUGCUGACCUGGAACAACAUCCAGCACACAGUAGUAAUCAAUGUGUUUUUGAAUGAAUGAGUGGACACCUUACCCAGGAUAAUAAUUCAUGCUUAUUGAUAAAGGCAGACAAACCAGGGUUAUAAGUUAGAACCCAGAGGAAGCCUAGGGGUGGGAGGAUUCAGGGUAUCACAACUGUAUCUGAGAAUGAGGAGGUUGUAGGAGGAGGCCUUUCGGAUAGCACCCCCUAGUUCUGCCCCUCAUAUCUGCUUCCUUGGUCUCUCCUGAUUACUUGCUGUUUCUUUUCUUUUUUUGGAGCAUCUCACAGAUACGUUUAUUCAUACCACAAAGUAAACACUAUUCAGUCUGCAGAUCUCCAGGGGAGCCCACCAGCCUAGUCAACAUGGCCUCGGAAGACAUUGCCAAGCUGGCAGAGACACUUGCCAAGACUCAGGUGGCCGGGGGACAGCUGAGUUUCAAAGGCAAGAGCCUCAAACUCAACACUGCAGAAGAUGCUAAAGAUGUGAUUAAAGAGAUUGAAGACUUUGACAGCUUGGAGGCUCUGCGUCUGGAAGGCAACACAGUGGGCGUGGAAGCAGCCAGGGUCAUCGCCAAGGCCUUAGAGAAGAAGUCGGAGUUGAAGCGCUGCCACUGGAGUGACAUGUUCACGGGAAGGCUGCGGACCGAGAUCCCACCAGCCCUGAUCUCACUAGGGGAAGGACUCAUCACAGCUGGGGCUCAGCUGGUGGAGCUGGACUUAAGCGACAACGCAUUCGGGCCCGACGGUGUGCAAGGCUUCGAGGCCCUGCUCAAGAGCUCAGCCUGCUUCACCCUGCAGGAACUCAAGCUCAACAACUGUGGCAUGGGCAUUGGCGGCGGCAAGAUCCUGGCUGCAGCUCUGACCGAAUGUCACCGGAAAUCCAGUGCCCAAGGCAAGCCUCUGGCCCUGAAGGUCUUUGUGGCUGGCAGAAACCGUCUGGAGAAUGAUGGCGCCACUGCCUUGGCAGAAGCUUUUAGGGUCAUCGGGACCCUGGAGGAGGUCCACAUGCCACAGAAUGGGAUCAACCACCCUGGCAUCACUGCCCUGGCCCAGGCUUUCGCUGUCAACCCCCUGCUGCGGGUCAUCAACCUGAAUGACAACACCUUCACUGAGAAGGGCGCCGUGGCCAUGGCCGAGACCUUGAAGACCUUGCGGCAGGUGGAGGUGAUUAAUUUUGGGGACUGCCUGGUGCGCUCCAAGGGUGCAGUUGCCAUUGCAGAUGCCAUCCGCGGCGGCCUGCCCAAGCUAAAGGAGCUGAACUUGUCAUUCUGUGAAAUCAAGAGGGAUGCUGCCCUGGCUGUUGCUGAGGCCAUGGCAGACAAAGCUGAGCUGGAGAAGCUGGACCUGAAUGGCAACACCCUGGGAGAAGAAGGCUGUGAACAGCUUCAGGAGGUGCUGGAGGGCUUCAACAUGGCCAAGGUGCUGGCGUCCCUCAGUGAUGACGAGGACGAGGAGGAGGAGGAGGAAGGAGAAGAGGAAGAAGAGGAAGCAGAAGAAGAGGAGGAGGAAGAUGAGGAAGAGGAGGAAGAAGAGGAGGAGGAGGAGGAAGAAGAGCCUCAGCAGCGAGGGCAGGGAGAGAAGUCAGCCACGCCCUCACGGAAGAUUCUGGACCCUAACACUGGGGAGCCAGCUCCCGUGCUGUCCUCCCCACCUCCUGCAGACGUCUCCACCUUCCUGGCUUUUCCCUCUCCAGAGAAGCUGCUGCGCCUAGGGCCCAAGAGCUCCGUGCUGAUAGCCCAGCAGACUGACACGUCUGACCCCGAGAAGGUGGUCUCUGCCUUCCUAAAGGUGUCAUCUGUGUUCAAGGACGAAGCUACUGUGAGGAUGGCAGUGCAGGAUGCAGUAGAUGCCCUGAUGCAGAAGGCUUUCAACUCCUCGUCCUUCAACUCCAACACCUUCCUCACCAGGCUGCUCGUGCACAUGGGUCUGCUCAAGAGUGAAGACAAGGUCAAGGCCAUUGCCAACCUGUACGGCCCCCUGAUGGCGCUGAACCACAUGGUGCAGCAGGACUAUUUCCCCAAGGCCCUUGCACCCCUGCUGCUGGCGUUCGUGACCAAGCCCAACAGCGCCCUGGAAUCCUGCUCCUUCGCCCGCCACAGUCUGCUGCAGACGCUGUACAAGGUCUAGACUCAAAGCCUCUCCCAUCCCUUGGCCUGGACCAGUGAGCUGGGGAGGGACUCGGAUGAACUGAGGCGCAGCCUACGCCAUUGCCUUGGACAGGACUCUGGCCACAGGCAGGGCGGGUCUGUGUCCCAUGUGUCCUGUCAGUCCCCUGAGUAUGUGUGUGGGUGUGGCGCAUGUGCAGGUCUGUGCCUCCUGUCGGGAUUUGGGUUUUAACGUCUUCUGCUGGCCCAGCCCUGCUCUGUUGUGGGGAGUUGGCCCCCAGGGGAAAGGGCUGUGAGCUGCUCCGCCAUUAAACUCACCUCCACCUGAGGGCGCUCUGCUGAUCUCCGCCUGGGCCCUGAUGGCCGUCCCCACCCACCUGCCUUCCGGCCCGGCUCCCUGGCGGAGCCAGAACCCAGGGAGUUGCCCGCGUGCUGUCCUUCCCCUCUGUGUUGUGAUUGGGUUGUUUCCUGCCCUGCCUGGGGCUGCUUCUCGUCACCAAGCCCUGGUCCUGCGGCAGCUGUCACCCCUACCAUCCAUACCACUGUGCUGACCGCUCAGCCUGAAGAGCAGAGAAUGCCAUGGGUGGGACUGUGGGGGUCGGAUCGUGGGGUUGUUGGCAGAGGGCAACCCUGGGCCCCACACCGUGUGGACAGGCAGACACCAGAUUGUCCAGGAGCAGGAGCUGCUGGGACUGCGCUGGCCCCGGACCUAGUGGGCCUUCUCCUGGCUGCUGAGAUGUCGUCUGUGACUGGCCUGGCUGGAGGGGGAGUGUUGACAACCCAAAGCUGUUCUCCAGUCUGGGGAGGGAGAGGCAGGGUCCCCAAUGUCCGAGCUGCAUCUGGACGCUGCUCUUAAAGGACCUCCUGGGGCAGGGGAGCGGUAGGGUCUGGACUGGGCAGAUGCUGUAUGACCUCCCUGAGCACCCGUGACUGCCCCAUGCUUUCCCCUUUGUGCUCUGUGUGUGUCUGGGCUGUGCCCGGGGGCUUCACAAAUAAAGUCGUGUGGCAGCUUCAGAGACUCAGAAACUCUCACUGAAAGCGGGAUAGUCUCGGGGGCCGUUGUACGUGGAGUCCCACCUCGGCAGAGCAUGCGGCCCCGCAGCAGUCUGUGGGGCAGUCAGCCCUGCAGAAGGGCCCGGCCUCGGCCUCAGGCCACUACCUGGGAAGUGGCAGUCCUGAGUGGGGGCCCAUUUUCCUGCCUGGCCACACCUCACCCAGCACCCUGCCUUUGGGCUGCAGCUCGCUUGGCUUCUGCGUUGCUCCUUCACUAUGGAAGCCACCUCCCUUGGGAUCCUUUGCUCCACUGCCACAUAUGUGAGGACAGCCCAGCCAACCUUCCUUACCUCCUACCCUACACCAUGUAUGUGCUUUGGGAGCCCAUGUCCCCCACAAACGGCCUCCAAGAAGUCCCUCCAAGGUUUCUUAGAGGGCAAUAUUUUCUCAUUGGCAGUCGGCCACGUAGGUGACCAGGUGGCAGAGGAUACUGCUGGCCCUGUCCCCUGUCUUCUGUGUGAGUUGAUACGGUAGGGGGUGGGUGUGGGGCUGGCAUUAAGUUCUGAUGCCAGCUACAACGUGGAUGAACUUUGAAAACAUGUUAAAUGAAAUAAGCCAGACACAAAAGGACAAAUAUGAUUCCAUUUAGAUGAGGCAUCUAGAAUAAGCAAAUUCAGAGACAAGAAGGUAGAGGUUGCCAGGGCUAGGGGAAGGGUGGAAUAGGGAGUGAGGCUGCAAACAGAUUCUCUGGGAUGAUGAAGAUGUUCUGGAAAUGGAGAGUGGUGAUGGUUGCAUAACAUUGUGAAUGUACUUAAUGCACUGAAUUGUACACAUAAAAAUGGUUAAAAUGAUA